UUAUUCUCUUUUCAGGCGUCCUAAUUCGCCAUUUUCCCUAGUUAGAAGUUGCCUUCUUCUCUUUAUAUAUUUGAUACUUUUAAUUGGCAUAAUCAAAUAUUUCAUUUGUAAAGUGCUAUUUAUUCAAUCAAUGAAUCUCUAUUUUGCACCCAGGAUCUUGGCCAGAGUGUUAAAGCCUGUGUCCUGGGGGAUAUUCCUGUUGUAAUAAAUGCUCCCAAAUCAAAAUUUACAUUCCCCCUCCCUUAAUCUGUAUCCUCUGGACUCAGUCCCAUAUAUACACCCUGCGUGCCUGCUGGUUCAAGAUGGCUGAUUCUGCAGCUCCUUUGGGAACACUCUCCUUCUUCCCUUAGCAGGGUAGCAGUUUCCCACACAGGCUAAGUUGUAAUGUGACCCUACUUAUUGAUCUGGUGGCCAGGAGGGUACUGGGGGGAAGGUCCUGAGGCAGGGCACGUGUUGCCUUGCAAAGCAGAGGAGGAGAGCUAGCCUUGUUGGGGAGCAGUGGGCCAUUUCUGUAGGCUCAGAGGGUUCCUGUGGACCUGGGCCUUCCAGGUCUCUGGCGUGUCUCUACCCAGACAUCCCCAUCCCACGUGUCAGAGCCUUCCUCCUUCCCUGGAUAGAAGACCAGCCAGGCUUGAGAAUUCAACCUUCCCUGGAGUUCUGCUGCCCAGAUAAUCAGGCCCUGGGCAUGAUCCUCAGCUCUCCCCGCCCUUCGGUUGUAGGAAAUGAGAUCCUUCAUAUGCUAACAAGGGCCUCUGACUCUGUUAAUUUGCUUUAAAUUGGUGAUUACCACCCUCAGCCUUCCUUGCCUUUUUCAGAUGCAACCAUGGCAUCCGGCAAUAGCCAUCUACCUUGCAAUAUUUAUAAUUACUCCUCCCUGUUCCUCAGUCAAGCGCACCAACCAGAAAAUUCCUUUCCACCUAUAUUCCAUCCUGAUUCACAGCCAGUGAGAUUUUAACAAGCACAUAUCAGCCACAGUAUGCCAGGGGCUUUCAGAACACCACCUUUCCACCAGCAAUGGGAUGCUCAGGGCCAGCCGCCUGGAGGGUGGCUUAGCCCUAAAAUCCCCUUUACAGCCCAUUUUCCUGGACCAUUAGCAACCAUCAUACUAGGUCAAGUUCCCCAGGAAGAAGACUAUUCGACUAAGAUUUGCAUGGAAAACUUUAUUCGGAGCAGAUCUGGGGACAAACACUGCAAGGCAGGGACACAAGUAGGUUCAAUCAGAGGAAGAGCCUAGAUGGCAGUGCAGCUUCCAGAAGAGACUCCACCCACCCCACAGGCAGCUUGCGCUCUCCAGAGUCCCCCCAGAUAGACAAGGGAGCUGCACCCAUUGACCAGUCUUUGAAUGCGAGAUCCCCAGAGAGGGGGACACUUGGGCAAAGCGGCUUGCCUCGGUCAUGAGCUGUGAGCCUGUGGCAGCUACUUCUCAUGGCAGCUGGGAGAAUGGGUGUCUCUGCCCUGAAGGCGGUGUCUCGGUAGCGCAGCACAGCAUCCCAUGUAGAAGACAUCUUGUCCAGGAAAUUGAAAAAUGGACCUUUGAAAAUGCUAGAUUUACAAUGAGAAAUGCCAUAAUUCAAGGUUUAUUCUAUGGGUCCUUGACAUUUGGGAUCUGGACAGCUCUGUUAUUCAUAUAUUUGCACCAUAAUCAUGUGAGCAGCUGGCAGAAGAAAAGCCAGGAGCCUCUGUCAGCUUGGUCCCCUGGAAAAAAAGUGCAUCAGCAAAUUAUCUAUGGCUCAGAGCAAAUACCAAAACCUCAUGUAAUAGUCAAAAGGACUGAUGAAGAUAAAGCAAAGUCUAUGUUAGGUACAGAUUUUAACCAUACAAACCCAGAACUUCAUAAAGAACUUUUAAAAUAUGGAUUUAAUGUGAUUAUCAGUAGAAGCUUGGGCAUCGAAAGAGAAGUGCCAGAUACCAGGAGUAAAAUGUGUCUUCAAAAACAUUACCCAGCCCGCCUCCCGACUGCCAGCAUUGUCAUUUGCUUCUAUAAUGAAGAAUGUAAUGCCUUGUUUCAGACCAUGUCCAGUGUCACGAACCUCACGCCACACUAUUUUCUUGAAGAAAUUAUUUUGGUAGAUGACAUGAGCAAAGUUGAUGAUUUGAAAGAAAAACUAGACUAUCACCUGGAAACUUUUCGGGGAAAGGUUAAAAUAAUAAGAAACAAAAAGAGAGAGGGGCUGAUUCGAGCAAGGCUGAUUGGAGCUUCUCAUGCUUCAGGGGAUGUUCUGGUGUUCCUGGACAGCCACUGUGAGGUGAACAGAGUAUGGCUGGAGCCCCUGCUGCAUGCCAUUGCCAAGGACCCCAAAAUGGUGGUGUGCCCCCUGAUAGAUGUCAUUGAUGAUAGAACUCUGGAGUAUAAGCCCUCUCCUCUUGUAAGGGGAACUUUUGAUUGGAACCUACAAUUUAAAUGGGAUAAUGUUUUCUCUUAUGAGAUGGAUGGACCAGAAGGAUCUACUAAACCAAUCCGGUCACCUGCAAUGUCUGGAGGAAUUUUUGCUAUACGUCGGCAUUAUUUUAAUGAAAUUGGACAGUAUGACAAGGAUAUGGAUUUUUGGGGAAGAGAAAAUUUGGAACUUUCACUAAGGAUCUGGAUGUGUGGAGGCCAACUCUUUAUAAUCCCCUGCUCUCGAGUAGGACAUAUCAGUAAGAAACAAACUGGAAAACCUUCUACAAUCAUCAGUGCUAUGACACAUAACUACCUAAGACUGGUGCACGUUUGGCUGGAUGAAUAUAAGGAGCAGUUUUUUCUUCGAAAGCCUGGUCUGAAAUAUGUCACCUACGGAAAUAUUCGCGAGCGUGUUGAGUUAAGGAAACGACUGGGUUGCAAGUCAUUUCAGUGGUAUUUGGAUAAUGUCUUCCCAGAGUUGGAGGCAUCUGUGAACAGCCUGUGAAAGGAAAACAAAUCACUUUCAUUAAUAAAGGGUUAAAAGUCUCCUAGUCAUUCAACAUAGUGUCACAAGAGUGUAAGUUUGGAACAUCGUGGAAUUACGUGAAAUGCAAUUAAAAAAAUAUGACCAGA